AGACGGCAGCGGCGACAUGGCUUCGGAGCAGGACGUGCGCGCCCGGCUGCAGCGCGCUGGCCAGGAGCACCUCCUGCGCUUCUGGGCCGAGCUGGCGCCGGAGCCACGAGCCGCGCUGCUGGCGGAGCUGGCGCUGCUGGAGCCCGAGGCGCUGCGCGAGCACUGCCGGCGGGCGGCGGAGGCCUGCGCGCGCCCCCACGGCCCGCCGCCCGACUUGGCCGCGCGCCUGCGGCCCCUGCCCCCAGAGCGCGUGGGCAGGGCCAGCCGCAGCGACCCCGAGACACGGCGGCGCUGGGAGGAGGAAGGUAAGCGGGGUGGGAGGCCCUGGGGGCCGGCAGGGGGUCGUGCCCACGGAGCGGGUGGGAACCGAGGCCGCGCUCGGGGAACUGUAGUUCUCCUCGCUACUUUGAGACGUGUCUCGCCUCACGCGUUCCGGCCCCCGAGUCCUGGCGCCCCAGCCCCAGAGUUGGUUUCCCCUAAAGCGGAAGGGUGGGCGGGUCCCGGGCGUCCCUUCACGGCGCCCGUACCCCCAGGUUUCCGUCAGAUUUCUCUGAACAAGGUGGCCGUCCUGCUGCUGGCUGGGGGGCAGGGCACUCGCCUGGGCGUGACCUACCCCAAGGGUAUGUACCGUGUGGGGCUGCCCAGCCGGAAGACCCUGUACCAGCUGCAGGCGGAGCGGAUUCGGCGGGUGGAGCAGCUGGCCGGUGAGCGCCACGGGACCCGCUGCACCGUCCCCUGGUACGUCAUGACCAGCGAGUUCACUCUGGGGCCCACGGCCGAGUUCUUCAGGGAGCACAACUUCUUCCACCUGGACCCCGCCAACGUGGUCAUGUUUGAGCAGCGCCUGCUGCCUGCUGUGACCUUUGAUGGCAAGGUUAUCCUGGAGCGGAAAGACAAAGUUGCCAUGGCCCCAGACGGCAACGGGGGCCUCUACUGCGCGCUGGAGGACCACAAGAUCCUGGAGGACAUGGAGCGCCGGGGAGUGGAGUUUGUGCACGUGUACUGUGUGGACAACAUCCUGGUGCGGCUGGCGGACCCUGUCUUCAUCGGCUUCUGUGUGUUGCAGGGCGCAGACUGUGGCGCCAAGGUGGUGGAAAAGGCAUACCCCGAGGAGCCCGUGGGCGUGGUGUGCCAGGUGGACGGUGUCCCCCAGGUGGUGGAGUACAGCGAGAUCAGUCCUGAGACCGCACAGCUACGUGCCUCCGACGGGAGCCUGCUGUACAAUGCAGGCAACAUCUGCAACCACUUCUUCACCCGAGGCUUCCUUAAGGCGGUCACCAGGGAGUUUGAGCCUUUGCUGAAGCCACACGUGGCUGUGAAGAAGGUCCCGUAUGUGGAUGAGGAGGGGAAUCUGGUAAAGCCGCUAAAACCGAACGGGAUAAAGAUGGAGAAGUUUGUGUUUGAUGUGUUCCGGUUUGCUAAGAACUUUGCUGCCUUGGAAGUGCUGCGGGAGGAGGAAUUUUCCCCACUGAAGAACGCAGAGCCAGCCGACAGGGACAGUCCCCGCACCGCUCGCCAGGCCCUGCUCACCCAGCACUACCGGUGGGCUCUGCGGGCCGGGGCCCGCUUCCUGGAUGCCCAUGGGGCCUGGCUCCCAGAGCUGCCCAGCUUGCCCCCAAAUGGAGACCCUCCGGCCAUCUGUGAGAUAUCGCCCUUGGUGUCUUACUCUGGAGAGGGUUUAGAAGUGUACCUGCAAGGCCGGGAGUUCCAGUCCCCGCUCAUCCUGGAUGAAGACCAGGCCAGGGAGCCGCAGCUGCAGGAGUCCUGACCCGCCCAGACUGUCCCCAGACUCCCCCGAGACCUGCCAGCCCCGGCAUCCUGGAAGUCCCGACUCCCCCCAGACCUGCCAGCCCCGGCGUCCUGGAGCUGGGGGCUACAGCCCAGCCUGAGCUCUGGGUGGGAAAGCAGCCUGCCCCAUGCUUCCAGCCUGCAGAACACAGAAUGAAACAUGCUGGUAGACUCCACGAGGGCAGGGCCUCUCCUGUCGCCUCUGGACACAAGUGGCGACAGCCUGCUGGGGGCUCUGUGGCUCCAUUCCUGGCUGUGGGGUCUAGUCAAGAGGCAGAGGGACUUGGGACCUGGGAGAAUGGGGCUGAGAGGAGGCUUCGGGUUGGGGCCCAAGGGAGGUGUGGUGUCAUCUGGGGAGAACAGGAGGGCAUGUCCCUUUGGGAGCCCGCCUUGUGGAUCCACCACACCCCACCGAGCACUAGAAGCUGCAUAAGCUACACAGGAUGUGCUUCUGCAGCCUACAGAUGCAGAACCAGAAUGAGGGGGACAAUUCCACCCACUCGAGGGCUGCCCCCUCUUCCUUAGCAGACGAACCAGUAAUGGGGGCAAGGCUGGGGCAUCCCAGCCCACACACCCUGGAUGCCCAGCAAGGCCACAGAAAGAGCCUGAUGUCCAUGAUCCAGGUGGCUCUGAGAAGCUUGGCCUGGACACCUGAGCCUGCGGCCGGUACUCCUGCCUUCUCCCCAUCUAUCCCCAAGGCCUCUGCCUCUCAGCCUCUUCCAUGGUCGGUUUAGGCUGCUGAGUUUUCUGUGCUUCCCCAAGAACCAGUGGGAUCAAUGCCGGCGGCCUCUGUGAUGGUUGCUGACUAAUCCGGGAUUUCAUGAGUCAGAGGCACCACCCCUCACCCCAGCUGCCUGCUGCUUCUGACGGAUCUUGGUGCUCAGGCUGCCUGGCUCUCCGAGUGAGGACGCAGCCUCCAUAUUUGGUGCACUCAGGCAUGGCUGGGACAAGCCAGCUGCCCCAGGGUUCUUCCCCUGGUGAUUCUCGCCUGCUUUCUCAUCUCAGGGGAGGCAGUGGCACCUCCCUCUCCCUGCUGACAUGAAGAGAGCUAUGAUAUGCCACUGCUGCCAACUCAUCCUCUGCCCCCACCUCGAAACCCACAGUCCCCAGUGGAGGGCCACUACUCAUCCCCAUUGGUUUCCCAGGGGAGGGGUGUUGUCUGGAAGGGCAGGUUCAGAUGCAGCCUUCCAGAUUUAGAGGCACUGGGAGGACAGUGGCUGAGUGGAGGCGCCCAGACCUGGGCAGGCAGCAGGCUCAGGCCCACACCUUGUGAUUUUUGAAACCAAAGCCCAGAAGAUGAUGUUUACUUCUCUCUCCCUGGCUCUGCCCUUCUUACUGCAAACCAUGCUGUGCCUUAGGGCCCUUCUCAUAGCUGUUCCUCAUGGCCAUGACUGGAACAGGGAUGCAACCUCUUUCUACACAAGCACAGUUAGUUGGGUGAAGUCUUUUUUUUUGUUUGUUUUAGACGGAGUUUCACUCUUGUUGCCCAGGCUGGAGUGAAGUGGCGUGACCUUGGCUCACUGCAACCUCCAGGCCAGCCUCAGCCUCCCUAGUAGCUGGGACUACAGGCACCCACUACCACGCCUGGCUAAUUCUUUGUAUUUUUAGUAGAGAUGGGGUUUGACCGUGUUAGCCAGGAUGGUCUCGAUCUCCUGACCUCGUGAUCCACCCACCUCGGCCUCCCAAAGUGCUGGGAUUAUAGGUGUGAGCCACCGCGCCGGGCCGGUUGCUGGCAUCUUAAUGUUCUGUAGGUGGAAUAUUUCCAAUAAACACAAGGUGCCGUAAUUGA